AGCGGAGGACCGAGCGACGGCCGGGAAUGGCAGCGCGGGGGCUCCGCGGAGGCGCCACGCACAGUGUCCAAAGCAUCCUUGCUUCCUCCUGGAAACCGCGGCCGCCAGAGGGUUCUUCCUGACUGUCCUCCACAUCAACUCUAUGCCUCUGAUCUCAGGCUAGGAGCCACUUCCUCUGGAAUACAAGCCUCACCCGAUUCUCUAGUGCAGUGAAUCAGAACCAGAAAAAGGCUAAAUGAUUCCCAGAGACACAGCCAUGAAGCAGGUGGUUUCGAUCUGAAAAAAUCAAGGUGAAAAGCUCUAGCAACCAGAAAGAAACGAAUGGAGGAAAAUGGAAAACGCAAGCUAGAAGACAGAGUCUCAUUCUGUAGGCCAGGCCGGAGGACGGGAAUGAGAAAGGCCAUGUACAAGAGGAAGUAGUCAGCCGCUAAAUCCAAGAUGGCGGGUGAAAAAGUUGAGAAGCCAGAUACUAAAGAGAAGAAACCCGAAGCCAAGAAGGUUGAUGCUGGUGGCAAGGUGAAAAAGGGUAACCUCAAAGCUAAAAAGCCCAAGAAGGGGAAGCCCCAUUGCAGCCGCAACCCUGUCCUUGUCAGAGGAAUUGGCAGGUAUUCCCGAUCUGCCAUGUAUUCCAGAAAGGCCAUGUACAAGAGGAAGUACUCAGCCGCUAAAUCCAAGGUUGAAAAGAAAAAGAAGGAGAAGGUUCUCGCAACUGUUACAAAACCAGUUGGUGGUGACAAGAACGGCGGUACCCGGGUGGUUAAACUUCGCAAAAUGCCUAGAUAUUAUCCUACUGAAGAUGUGCCUCGAAAGCUGUUGAGCCACGGCAAAAAACCCUUCAGUCAGCACGUGAGAAAACUGCGAGCCAGCAUUACCCCCGGGACCAUUCUGAUCAUCCUCACUGGACGCCACAGGGGCAAGAGGGUGGUUUUCCUGAAGCAGCUGGCUAGUGGCUUAUUACUUGUGACUGGACCUCUGGUCCUCAAUCGAGUUCCUCUACGAAGAACACACCAGAAAUUUGUCAUUGCCACUUCAACCAAAAUCGAUAUCAGCAAUGUAAAAAUCCCAAAACAUCUUACUGAUGCUUACUUCAAGAAGAAGAAGCUGCGGAAGCCCAGACACCAGGAAGGUGAGAUCUUCGACACAGAAAAAGAGAAAUAUGAGAUUACGGAGCAGCGCAAGAUUGAUCAGAAAGCUGUGGACUCACAAAUUUUACCAAAAAUCAAAGCUAUUCCUCAGCUCCAGGGCUACCUGCGAUCUGUGUUUGCUCUGACGAAUGGAAUUUAUCCUCACAAAUUGGUGUUCUAAAUGUCUUAAGAACCUAAUUAAAUAGCUGACUACAUUUUGUGUC